ACUCUGGCUGGGGAAGGCAUGAGUGACAGACCCACAGCAAGGCGGUGGGGGUAAGUCCUUCUUUGCCUUAAGGGAACAACGCUUAGGGCCAAAAGAUGAAACUGUCUCUUUUAUUAUAGAUGUUUGUGCCUUCUUAGGCAGAAUCUGGAAGGCAGCUAUAGGGCAGGUGGGUGGUUCUUUUAGAUCUGAGUACUGGGCAUUUUCAGAAGAGAGGCAUAGAGAAGGUAGAAGAAAAGGGAUGCUUUUUAGCCAAAUCCUCCAUAUGUUUCAGAUCUGCAAAAGCCCAGGAAAAUUACCCUAUGGAGGUGAAUCUAGCUAUAGUACAUUUCUUCGGAAAAAUUACUCACCCAGACGCUCAGCUGUCCUGGAGUGGAUGAAGCUGAGUGUUCAGCUAGAAAGUAAUGUGUCCGAUUCAGUACAUCAACAAACCCGCUUUGUUCUGGGGCAAAAGAAGCAAAUCUAAUUGUGUUGAUCAUUUCCAGUGACUGUGAACAUAUAAGGGAACACUGACAAUAAAAGCAGGGUGCUAUGGGUGACGCUAGGGUGAGCCCUCAUAAGGCCAGAGAUAUGUAUAUGCUGCCAGCAAACUUCACGGUUCACAGCCAAGUGAGGCUGGUCCAUCUGCCUUGGAAGAAGAUCAGAUUUUUGUGGAUUUAAAAAAAAAAAAAAGCUAAAAACAUUCUUAAAGAGCAUGUUUAUGUUUUGUGUUGGUGUUUUGCACUGUUUUAAAUUUCUCUGGUUGAUGAAUAUUUGAAGCUGAAAGAGCAACUACCUCUGGAGAGGUAAACAGGUGCAUGACAGGCCAAGCAGGGAGAGAACUCCGGAAAUGGCAGAAGUGAGAGGUGAAGGGGGUGAGCAGCGGGGCUGGCCUUUUCUGGGUCCCACCUCUUCUGGUGUCUCCUGCGGGGCUGAAAAGGACGUUUCCUGCCCACCUAGCUUCCUUAGCCUACUGUUUUGUCCUCCUCCUUCUCCCCUAACCCUGACCACAAACGACAGCACCUAUGAUCGCAUUUUGCCCCCUUUGCCAUCCCGGCUACAGCCCUGGGCUGCCGGUGAGUUCAGAAGUGACUCUCCUAACUUCUUCAAUAUGUGACUUUUCUGAGUUUACCGUCUUUGGGAAUAUUUUUAGUGUCUCCUCCAGGGUGCCCUCCCUGCCCCAUUGCAACCAUCGUUUUUGUCUCUUUACAUUCUUUUCCUCUAGAGAGUAUGAUGUCGUUGUCAUCCCACCUGGGGUUUUUCAUACUUCUGAGAUUCGCUUCACUGGGGCAGGGGAUGCGUGGGAUGUGGCUGGCCACCCCCCUGUGGAGCCAGCUCUUCCUUUAUCCUGCCACCCGGGCCUGGGCAAGAAAGGGUUUUUCUCUCUCCACCUCUAAAGCAAAGCCCCAUAGCAAACUAAGGGCUAGGCUGAGCUGGAAAUUCCCCUCACCCUUUUUGGCACUGCAUUUCCUCACUACCCACGCAGAAAGCAGGUUCCCGGGAACAUUCAGUGACAUGGGGAAAUGAGGGCCCCGCAAUUUGUCAAAGGGAAAGCCACAAUAAUACUAAUCUCUUAAAGUACUUGGCUUUCUUGCCUAACCCCUUACGUGGUCCUCUGCAAUUAGAUUCUCUGGUAAAUACUCUCCAUACUUCUUGGCUCUCAUGACUAUCACAGGCAAAGGACAAGGGCAAAAGUCUUAGAUGAUAGGGUAACUGGGGUAAUUGCCCCCCCCCCCCAAAAGGGGAAUCCUAGCCAUUUCCUGCCAGAAUGAGCAGUUGGCAUCAAUAUCGUCAAACCACCCCUUCUCUGCUCCAAAGAUCUAAUGACAGCAAGAGGGAUAUAGACGGGAGGAGAAGGCGUCCUCCCUCUCCCAGACUCCCUGCCCACCACCCUCCCCAGAGAAGCUCCACAAGGUGAGACACACUGUCCUAUAGGCCCAUGUAACAGAAAGCCAUCAAAAAGACCGUAGAGAAAAGCCGUUUUCCAUAGAGCCUUCUGCUCAGGGGCCCACAGUUUCCCUAACCACACCCGCUUUUCCUGACUUCCCGAGCUCUGCACCAUGAAGGCAGGAAAGGUACCGGGGCAUUGCUGGCACACCCCAGCCUCCAGGCUCCCUUUGGCAGGUUUAUCUGCAUUGUACGGUCAGGGUCAAGGGGUGAGAGAGGGUCGGGCACGAGGAGAGGCUGUCCUUCCUCCCCUAAAAGCAUCCCCCACUCCCAUCUCUCCCCACCUCCAGCGGCCAGGAUGCACCGGGCCGGCGGGCAGGCGGGCGAGCUCGCGGGGCCGCUUCUGCGUGUGCACCUGGCCGCCGCCCGGGAGCCUGCCACGGGCCGGGAAUGGCCGCUGCUCCGCCCUCUGAGAGGUGCUCCAGGCUCCCUGGGGACGGAGGUUUACACGUCCCCGUGCCGCGCUCCCAGAUCUGGGCGGUGCGCGUGUCCCUUGGGCAGGCUCAGCUCCCGGACUCCUCCCGCUGGCAGCCUGCUCGUUCCUGGCGCAAAGGAGAGGGAGGGAGUGUCGCUGUCCCAGCUGAGGCCCUGCCUGUUCCCAUCGCCCUUGCUAGUCACCAGAAGCUCCUCUCCCCUCAAUGAGUUCACUUUCUCAAAAGACAGCCUUCAGCACCCUGGUUUCCUAGAAGGCUUCCCCCUAAUCCAGAGUCUGGGGGGAGGGGGAGAUUUUCAGAAUGCCAUUUCAAAGCAAUCAAAUGCAAAGCUAGAAAAGACGACCCCCCCCCCCCACGCACACCUUGUUUUAAUGCUUUAUGUUCGAAAUUAAGUGUGGACCUUUGUGUACCAGAGAGAACAUCAUGGUGGCUUUCAAAGGGGUCUGGACUCAAGCUUUCUGGAAAGCAGUCACAGCGGAAUUUCUGGCCAUGCUUAUUUUUGUUCUCCUCAGCCUGGGAUCCACCAUCAACUGGGGUGGAACAGAAAAGCCUUUACCGGUCGACAUGGUUCUCAUCUCCCUUUGCUUUGGACUCAGCAUUGCAACCAUGGUGCAGUGCUUUGGCCAUAUCAGCGGUGGCCACAUCAACCCUGCAGUGACUGUGGCCAUGGUGUGCACCAGGAAGAUCAGCAUCGCCAAGUCUGUCUUCUACAUCGCAGCCCAGUGCCUGGGGGCCAUCAUUGGAGCAGGAAUCCUCUAUCUGGUCACACCUCCCAGUGUGGUGGGAGGCCUGGGAGUCACCAUGGUUCAUGGAAAUCUUACCGCUGGUCAUGGUCUCCUGGUUGAGUUGAUAAUCACAUUUCAAUUGGUGUUUACUAUCUUUGCCAGCUGUGAUUCCAAACGGACUGAUGUCACUGGCUCAAUAGCUUUAGCAAUUGGAUUUUCUGUUGCAAUUGGACAUUUAUUUGCAAUCAAUUAUACUGGUGCCAGCAUGAAUCCCGCCCGAUCCUUUGGACCUGCAGUUAUCAUGGGAAAUUGGGAAAACCAUUGGAUAUAUUGGGUUGGGCCCAUCAUAGGAGCUGUCCUCGCUGGUGGCCUUUAUGAGUAUGUCUUCUGUCCAGAUGUUGAAUUCAAACGUCGUUUUAAAGAAGCCUUCAGCAAAGCUGCCCAGCAAACAAAAGGAAGCUACAUGGAGGUGGAGGACAACAGGAGUCAGGUAGAGACGGAUGACCUGAUUCUAAAACCUGGAGUGGUGCAUGUGAUUGACGUUGACCGGGGAGAGGAGAAGAAGGGGAAAGACCAAUCUGGAGAGGUAUUGUCUUCAGUAUGACUAGAAGAUCGCACUGAAAGCAGACAAGACUCCUUAGAACUGUCCUCAGAUUUCCUUCCACCCAUUAAGGAAACAGAUUUGUUAUAAAUUAGAAAUGUGCAGGUUUGUUGUUUCAUGUCAUAUUACUCAGUCUAAACAAUAAAUAUUUCAUAAUUUACAAAGGAGGAACGGAAGAAACCUAUUGUGAAUUCCAAAUCUAAAAAAAGAAAUAUUUUUAAAAUGUUCUUAAGCAAAUAUAUACCUAUUUUAUCUAGUUACCUUUCAUUAACAACCAAUUUUAACCGUGUGUCAAGAUUUGGUUAAGUCUUGCCUGACAGAACUCAAAGACACGUCUAUCAGCUUAUUCCUUCUCUACUGGAAUAUUGGUAUAGUCAAUUCUUAUUUGAAUAUUUAUUCUAUUAAACUGAGUUUAACAAUGGCAAAAUACAGUAUGUCACAGUCAUGCACAUUCAAGAGAGAAAAUAUAACAAGUUCUUUUAUGAGCAAUCCCUUAUGCAUAGACUACCUUGGCAAAAGAGCAUUAGCAAGUGUCACUGCUCAUCAGUUACUUCCUUCCAUUUAUAUCACAAAUACCCAAGUUUCAAUUCUAACUUCAUUUCAUGGUAUUUCUUCCUCCUCAAUGCCCAAGGUAAUGUGGGACUAAAGCCCAGAAAUUUGAAAAGAAUAUUCAGAAAUCCUUCCCAAAUCAUAAGGGCACCUAUUGAGAUUCAAGACAAGCAGACUCGUAAAAUCUUGUAGAGGCAGAGGCAAAGUUAUCAUCAUACAAAAAUCACAAACAAAAAGGAGAUCUGUAUUCGGGUAUCAAACGGUUGAUCUGUUUUCAGUGCACACCCUCAAAUGCACCACACCAGUUUUACGAUCUAAGCUUUUAACCCCUUUACCACUUUGCUUAUUUUUAAAAAAUUUAUUGGCAAAACUGGGGAUUUUGUUUGUAACUUUGGUUAUCUAUAUUUAAACAUUAGCUGAGACAUAUUUUUGAUAACAAGAACUUAGCUAGUUGAGUCCUGGCUUUUUGUUGAUUAUUAAGCUGUGUUCACUCUAGAAGGUGUAAAGGCCCUGUCCCAAUCUCUGCUCUCUCACUUCUCGUGACAUUUGUUGAUAAUCUUUACUGCAAGUGUAAUGAUAUUUGAGUGAAUUAAAAUGCAUGACAGACAAGGUACAACAUGGUUGCAGAAUAAAAGGGUGAGGACAUCAGAUCACUCUGUAUUCAAAGCUUACUAGACGAACAAUCUUUCAUUUCUGGAUAUAUUGUAGCUAACCCAACACAUUUUUAAACUAUUUUUGUUACUGACUCACUUACUUGUCAAAAUAAUUGGUUUUUCUGUCCUGCUUUGCCUUUUGUCACUAGAAUGUUCUCCAGAAACCCCAGUUUCUGUCAUCUUAACUGUCUAGUCUAGCCGUUAACUUAGACAAAGAAGUGCAAAUGUCAAUUUCACUAAACAAAAGCUAUUAGAAGUAAAGCAGAAACCUAUCACUGCAAGGAGUGACUUGUAAAUAACUGAUGAUCAAGGGCUGUCUUCUCUCAAGCAUGGUUCCAACUCUGUGUCACUUUUUAGCGUUAAUGGCAGUUGUGUGUCUGUGGCAGUGAGAUAAUGGACCACUAUUAAACCUGAUUCUCUUCGGUGCUAGGAAAGAGUGAUGUGUGAGAUUCCCAGAGAGUCGUCACACCAGUGUUAUGCCUGGGAGUGCCACUGGCAUACCGCAGGUGCCUAAAUCCCAGGCCCCUUUCUCAGGGGGCGUGGCCACACCACACACUGCGCCAGUGACACAUAGUUACUUCCUGGCUGGGACGGCACCUAUAGAAACUAGGGUACAAAUCUCCCAAAGAUGGUUUGCACCGUCAUUUCAAAUGUUUGCACAAUAUACCACUUAGAGGCUUAAAAUCAGGGUGGUUCAGUUCAAAAGGUAAUAUCAACCGUCAGCAAACAUGUCAGUUUAAAAAUAAGUUCGGUUAACAAGGAAGUGUUAAGCAGAUUUUUUGAAUACACUUACAAUAUACUGGCUUAUAAUCAUUUUUAUUCUGCCAUAUGGUUUAUUUCAUAUACACUCACUUUUACACUCACUUCCAAUUAUAGCAUUCAAUAAGUUACGGUUAAAGAAAAGUGAAUGGUGUUUUUGUAAUUUGUUUUCUAGUAGCUAGCAGAGAGCCUGGCACAUAGUAUGUAUUCAAAACAAGUGUGUUAAUUAAUAAAAAUAUAUAAAUCUCAUUUGAGAUUUAAGAAUAUAAAUAAUUUUCUUUUAAUCUUUAUUUUGCUCAAUAUUUAAUAGGAAGUAUGAUUUCAAGGACUACUAAAGGAAGGCAAUAUACAUGUGAAAACCAUAAAAUACAUUUUUUGCAUUCUACUAUUUUUAGGGGCAUGAAAUGAAUGAAAGCUUUAGCACUUUUUUGCCCCUACAUAUGAGACAACAUAUUUUGUAUUUCACUCAAGGCUCUGCCAGUAAAAAGUAAUGAAAUUGUACCUUUCUAAUGACAUCUAUGCAGCAGGGGUCUAUCGCCUUGUGGAUGGCACCAAAUUAUCCAAGUGUAUUAGGAGACUGGGGCUUUUUUCUUUAAUCCCUUCUUAUUAAUGAAGUGCAUAGUGCUGCUCCCAGGAGACCACUGCUGACAGAUACACAGAGAAGAGAUCAGAGAGGAAAAACUGGGAAGACAUAAAUGAAUUAUACCCAGCCAUGAAACAAUGCCAACUGUCUCUUCCCUAAGGAAGAGUACAAGUACCCUAAAAUUGAAAGGUGGUCCCUACACUGAAAACGCACAUAGUUUGUCAAAAGUGUACAAAAGGGAAAGAGUCUUAUUUUAAGCUUUCAGGCUUUCUUAAAAACUUGGGGACCAGAAUUUCAAUGUAUGUUUCCAUUGUUGAAGAUAACAUUUUCUUCAAAGAGCCUUAACCUUUUGUACUGGAAGGAAAUAUUUUCUGGACUUAAGUAGUUGCCUAAAUUUAAGAUUCCUACACUUUAUUUCUGCCAUUGAUGCUUUUCCUAAACCCUUAUACUAUCUUUUUAUUAUCUGAGCCUUUUCCUAAUGCAGCUCAUAGGUGCUAGCUAGAGCUGCUGCUCAGUAUUGAAGACUUUACAAGGAGAUUAGAAAUCUUUGGAAAACAUAUGUGAUGAAAUUGAGCUAUAUGAUUUAUCAGAGAUCUGAUUCCAAAGAGCACAGAAUACUGUUCUCAGACCAUGAAACCAGACAACACAUGUAUUGGUUUAAACUCGAUAAUGACAGGAAAAUUCCAAACUAGAGCAGUAAAUUCAAAUGGUAAGAUGAAUCCUAGAAGGCCUCUGAUUGCAGCAUGUUGACACCAACCUCACGUUACGAACAAUUCACAGAGAAUUUGCCUUUGUGGCAACUGAAGAUGGAAGUCUGGGGGGCACAGACAACCUUAUCAAACAAUAUAAAAGCCAAUAUAAAUUCUCAUAAGCACUAUAGAAUUUGCAAAUUCAGAACAUUUUAUACCUAAAAGUAAUUCUGUCUUUCCUAAAGUGUUUUUAACAUGAAAAUUAGUAGGAAGAUGUGGUUACUAUUUGGAAAGUGUAAUGUAACAAAACUCUCUUUUGUUACCACAAAUUUUGUGAGUUUAGUACUCUACAGAUUGCCCCAUAAGAGCAGUAGCUUUUGAAACUCAUAAUUCUCUGAAAUAAAUGAAAGACAUUUAAUUCAAGGAUCAAAAAUUGUGGCCAUCUUUGCAAAUGACUACCUAUAGCCUGUGAAAAUACAUUUCAAAAAAUGUUAUGUGCAAUGAACACUAAAUUUAAGAGCAGUUACAGUGUGACUCACUCAUGUUUAAAAAAAAUCGAAGAGCUAAAAAAUACGUCUAAUUUAUGUAACCCAUUGGAAUGUAUUUCUAGGUUCUCUUCAGGAUUAAUUAAAUAAACAUGCAAUUUAUGAAAACAUAUAAACAAUUAUUUAUCACUUUUAUGACCCAAAUCACAAUAAAAUUGUCAUUUAGGAUAAACUGGGGAGAAUAGACUGAACAUAUGGUUAUAUUCACAGUUAUUUAUUAACUUAAAUGUUAUUCCAACAUUAGAGCUAAUGUUAAAAAGAUUUAAACUGUAACGUCUAAUAUUUGGAAUAAUAUAUUAAAGUAUUAGCACUGUGGUUGAUUUUCUUGAAUUAUGUUGCAUCUUGUACUACUAAGCUUGUGAAAAUAAACAUUUGGAUGUUUUAAAAGGUAAACAUUA